UUGGGGUGGGGGUGGGGUGCUGCAGGCCAGGGAAGCUCCUUUUGUGCCCCAGCGGGGGGUCUGAGGGGAGAUCCAAACCCCGGCACUCUCCCUUGCCUCCCUUCUGGCACAGCCCACCCAGAGACACUGUUGCACCUAGGGCGGUCCAGGGGUGAAUGUAGCACCCCAGGCCCCAGCCCUCCACCAGGAGGACAGUCCCAUGCAUUCACUGCUAAUAAGCACUGGAUGCGGAUGGCAGAUCAUGUGACCCCAGCUGGAAGUUCAUCCUGAAGUCUCGCUGAAAUACCUCCUGCUGCAGCCAGCCGGGGGCUGCACGAGUGUGGCUGGGCAGGUUCUAUUCCCCUGGUAUCCUCUGUCCUCGGGGAGGCUUCUGGGAAUAAAGUCCCAUUAACAGAGGUGCAGAAAGACGCUUAGAGUCAGUCUCUGCUCCAGGACCCUUCUCUUCUCAGGCUGGGGCUGAAGUCAGGGCCUAGAGGCUGCCACUGGACAGGUGCCUCGAAGGGGCAUCAGCUAGGGCCUGGGGAGACCUAGGUGUCACUUCUUGCAGAAGGCAGGGAAAGGGGCAGACCCACAGUGAGAGAGAGGUGGUUGGACUCUGGCCAUGAGAACUGCACCCGCUGAGGCCCCCUCUGCCGGAGUUGCUCAGGGCAGUGAACCUUGGAAGCGCCACACUGGUCCUGAUGUUUAGCAUGUGGCACAGUGACCAGGAGGAGGGACACAGGUCUGGUGGGAAGGGAGGGAACCUGGAUAUGUCCGGCUCUGAGACUCGACUGUCACGGCCCCUUGUGCCAAGUCCUCCCAUCCCCUGCCCUGCCCGGACCCCGUUCCUGGGAUCGGAGGGAGCCCCCCGCCCCACCCCACUUUCUCCCAGGUCCACAGCUUCCCCAGGCCAGCGGAGCAGAGUGUAGGCCAGCUUGGGUCCUACAGCACUAGCCAAGGGAGCUGAGGGGAGGCAGGGAUGAGGGCAUCUGGGGGAGCCCAGUGAGGGAAGAUGAGCUGACCUGUGUGAGUGCAGGGUCCCUGCCUCCCAGAGUUGCCACCCACCAGUCUCUCCUCAGCCUCCUUAGUGUGACGAUUUCUGCCUCCAGAAGCAUCCCUGGGUAACAGUGAGCCGGACAGCUCCAAGAGCCUGCCUAGGUGUGAGGGGGAGACACAGUCCCAUCCCCCCAUGCUUGACAGUCCUGGCAGCUGUCUCUGAAGGUAGUGAGUCCCCAUUUCUAGGUGCUGAGCAGAAGGUAACAUGGUAAGGAUGCUGUCAGUUGAGAGCUGGGGGUGGCCUGGGACUCCCUGGUCCCGUCUGUGCUCAGGGACAGGAAUGUGCUGCACAGAGACGCUGGGUGUGGGAGCUCGUGUUUGUAAGGAGUCUGAAGCUGACCCCUCGGGUACUGGAGUCCUGGGGUUCUCAGGGGAUCCUGCAUACAGAGGGCAAGGACGUGCGUGUACUCUAGUGUAUGUCCAGCCCACGCGUGUGCACAUAUUCACGCGUGGGUACUUGCACACAGGGCAGGUGGAUUGUGGGUAAGGAGCACCAGCCCUGUGUGUGGAGUGGGUGUGCAAAGAGGUGUGUUCUGGCACGCACAGAGGGCAGUGUGCACGCAGCACUGGAGCCAGGCGUGCUGUGUCCCAGGGGAGGGUGGCGGCCUGGUGCCUCCUGGAAGGUGUGGGCCUGGGAGGAGCCUUCUUCUGACUUUGGACUUGGAAACUGCUUCCUCCUGGGCUCAAAGACUUUUGAAAAGGGUGUAUGGGGCUGUGCUAGGGGGCAUCCUGUCCCCAGCCCUGCCUCUCACCCCCCAACCCCUAGGCACUGGAAUAGCAGGGCCACAGGUACUCAGGAGGGCUUGGCAUGUGGGGCCGUGAAAGGAGAGGCAUGGAACCAACACCAUCCACAUUUCCUUACCUCUGUUCCCACAUGGCCAGUGCUGGCCCCACUGAUCUGCACCAGACUGUCCUUAGUGUCUCUGCUCCCCACCCCACCCAACCUGCCCCAUCCCUGGCAUAGCUGAGCCCCGAUCCUUAGCAUCUGGGGAGACAGAGGUGAGGAACAUGUCCCCCUGGGAGCUGUAGGUCCAGGGAGACCCUGUGGGUGAGGAUGCUCUCCCAGAGGCCAGCAUGGCACAGAGGCUUCCUGCAGGAGGGGGCACUCGGCCAGCCCUUCGCAGUACAGAGAAGGCCUCUGAGGGGGCGGGGAGCCGGCGAGCUGCAGGGAGCAUGCUGGGCACAGCAGGUACCUGGAGUGGGAAGGAAGGUUAGGACCAGGUAGGGCAGAGGAGCGGAGGGGCUGAGGACUGGGCUCUGCACUGCCGGGCACCUGCUGGGGUGGGUAGGAGAGAGCAGGGAGGGGCGCGUGCCCACUCUGCAGAGGAGCCUGCUCCAUGGUGGUGGCUGCCGCAGGAGCAGCGGUUGCCUGGCACCUCUGCUGUUGCCAUGGUGACGAUGGAGGUGCUAACUUGCUAAUGAAUCCCCUUCGGCUGCAAAUAACAAUACUAUUGUGGGUGAUAGGCCCAGCUCCAGCUCAGCGUUGCUUAGGAGGCAGAGCAGGGCCAGGUAAAGGCCAGGACCCGUCCUCCCGCCCCUCCAGCCCCUGCCCACCACCCUGCAGCUGGACUUGCCCUCCUCCCUCCCCUCCCUCUGGGUCUCAGAUCUGGCUGGCUGCACCGAGGUCUCUCAUGGCAGUGUCAGGACUCAGGGCUGCAUGAAGGCUAGGCCCUGGCUGCAGAGAGGGCGAGGGCCUCUCCUCACACCUGCCCUCCUCCCUGCACUGGGGGGUAUUUGCUUCUGUUGUUUUCAGUGAGAGAGAAUCCACCCCCACUUAACGGAUGAGGACAUUGAGGCCGGGGCAGCUCCUCAAAAGACCCCCAGCCCAAGUGUCCCUGCCACUGCAGCCUUCUCGGGGUUCUGGGUCUCUGAGCUGGACCCUUGGGUAUCCUACGGGGCACCUGGAGCCGCUGUCUCACCAGAACCACACAUCUGGGCCCUCGCCUCUCACCACCUGUGCAAGGCUCAGGUCCAGCACCAUGUGCUAGGUCACUCCCAGCGCGAGGCCACACCUGGGCCGUCGGAGCAGCCCCUCCUCACUUCAGGGGUCACCCUCCCCAGCACCCAUUGCCCCACCAUGGCUGGGGACCGGCUCCCGAGGAAGGUGAUGGAUGCCAAGAAGCUGGCCAGCCUGCUGCGGGGCGGGCCUGGGGGGCCGCUGGUCAUCGACAGCCGCUCCUUCGUGGAGUACAACAGCUGGCAUGUGCUCAGCUCCGUCAACAUCUGCUGCUCCAAGCUGGUGAAGCGGCGGCUGCAGCAGGGCAAGGUGACCAUUGCGGAGCUCAUCCAGCCGGCUGCACGCAGCCAGGUGGAGGCUACGGAGCCACAGGACGUGGUGGUCUAUGACCAGAGCACGCGGGACGCCAGCGUGCUGGCCGCAGACAGCUUCCUCUCCAUCCUGCUGAGCAAGCUGGACGGCUGCUUCGACAGCGUGGCCAUCCUCACUGGGGGCUUCGCCACCUUCUCCUCCUGCUUCCCCGGCCUCUGCGAGGGCAAGCCUGCUGCCCUGCUACCCAUGAGCCUCUCCCAGCCCUGCCUGCCUGUGCCCAGCGUGGGCCUGACCCGCAUCCUGCCUCACCUCUACCUGGGCUCGCAGAAGGACGUCCUAAACAAGGAUCUGAUGACGCAAAAUGGAAUAAGCUACGUCCUCAACGCCAGCAACUCCUGCCCCAAGCCUGACUUCAUCUGCGAGAGCCGCUUCAUGCGGGUCCCCAUCAACGACAACUACUGUGAAAAACUGCUGCCCUGGCUGGACAAGUCCAUCGAGUUCAUCGAUAAAGCCAAGCUCUCCAGCUGCCAAGUCAUCGUCCACUGUCUGGCUGGCAUCUCCCGCUCUGCCACCAUCGCCAUCGCCUACAUCAUGAAGACCAUGGGCAUGUCCUCCGACGACGCCUACAGGUUCGUGAAGGACAGGCGCCCGUCCAUCUCGCCCAACUUCAACUUCCUGGGCCAGCUGCUGGAGUACGAGCGCAGCCUGAAGCUGCUGGCCGCCCUGCAGGGCGACCCGGGCACCCCCUCAGGGACGCCGGAGCCUCCGCCCAGUCCUGCCGCCGGGGCCCCGCUGCCACGGCUGCCACCACCUACCUCAGAGAGCGCUGCCACAGGGAAUGCGGCUGCCAGGGAGGGCGGCCUGAGCGCGGGCGGGGAGCCCCCCGCGCCCCCCACGCCCCCGGCGACCAGCGCACUGCAGCAGGGCCUGCGCGGCCUGCACCUCUCCUCGGACCGCCUGCAGGACACUAACCGCCUCAAGCGCUCCUUCUCCCUGGACAUCAAGUCUGCCUACGCCCCUAGCAGGCGGCCCGACGGCCCCGGGCCCCCCGACCCCGGCGAGGCCCCGAAGCUCUGCAAGCUGGACAGCCCGUCGGGGGCCGCGCUGGGCCUGUCCUCGCCCAGCCCGGACAGCCCGGACGCCGCGCCUGAGGCGCGCCCACGGCCCCGCCGGCGGCCCCGGCCCCCCGCCGGCUCCCCCGCGCGCUCCCCCGCGCACAGCCUCGGCCUGAACUUCGGCGAUGCGGCCCGGCAGACUCCGCGGCACGGCCUCUCGGCCCUGUCGGCGCCCGGGCUGCCCGGCCCUGGCCAGCCGGCCGGCCCCGGGGCCUGGGCACCGCCGCUCGACUCCCCAGGCACGCCGUCGCCCGACGGGCCCUGGUGCUUCAGCCCCGAGGGCGCACAGGGGGCGGGCGGGGUGCUGUUUGCGCCCUUCGGCCGGGCGGGCGCCCCGGGACCAGGCGGCGGCAGCGACCUGCGGCGGCGGGAGGCAGCGAGGGCUGAGCCCCGGGACGCGCGGACCGGCUGGCCCGAGGAGCCGGCCCCGGAGACGCAGUUCAAGCGCCGCAGCUGCCAGAUGGAGUUCGAGGAGGGCAUGGUGGAGGGGCGCGCGCGCGGCGAGGAGCUGGCCGCCCUGGGCAAGCAGGCGAGCUUCUCGGGCAGCGUGGAGGUCAUCGAGGUGUCCUGACCCCUCCGCUGCCCUCGGCCCCGCCGCCCGCAGCCAGGCCCGUUAUAAAUGUAUAUUAUAUAUAAUGCAAAGAAAGGUAAAUGGUUUUACUGGGAUUUUUAUCGAGAAGUAAAUAUUUCGAUUUUUUAUUUAUUUAAGCUGUUCAUUCUGGCAAUGAUUUGGCAACAGUGCGGGUGGUCCUCGAGCUCUAUUUUUACUGUCUGGUAUUUAAACUGAAACAUACGUUUCUAAGCAAUACGAGGCCACCUUCAGUCGCAAGCUGGGUGCCAGGCCUGGGGCCCCUCCCAGUUCCCCCGCCCCAGGAAACACUGCUGACCUUUGCAAAGGCUGCCGAGCUUUCGUGCACUUUUUACAUAACAAAAAGGUGAAAAAAAGGAAAAAAAAACUUCUUUGCCACAAACUGAGCCGCAGAACCCCCCUUCUCCCCCCACCCACCUCCCCUGCUCCCUCCCUUCUCUGCGCCGGCCUAGGGCUCUGCACCAAAGCCAUAGGAUGGAGGAGCAGGAGCUGGUGUGCCCCGGAGAGGUGCGGCCAGCCCUCCAUCAGCUCCAGGCACCAAAUCUUGGUGGCAAGGAGGGCACCCCGCUGCCCGUUGCCCCAGAGCUGUUCUCUGGCAGGGGAGGACAGGCAUUGGGCUUCAUGGUGCCAGGGUGUUCAGAGGGGCUGAGAAAUAGAACAGUGUGUGUAGGGGCUUCGGGCAGGGGGUUCUGGAACGUCAGAUGAGGUGCAGCCCAGGGGAGGACAGAGGUGUUAGUGCCCCCAACUCCUGCCAGAGCCCCAGUCCAGCCACAGAGUGGCUCAGAAAGGCCAUUCCUAGAGGGCUGCGGCCCUCCCUUCUCCCUUGCCCAUGCCCCCAGAGCUGCCUGCCGGGCAGGGUGGCACCAUUGCAGGAGAGGAGCUUGGCCUCCGGGGGUCAGGCAGGAGGCGCCUGGCUAGCCAGUGCUGGCUCCACUGGGCAGGAAGCCCUGGACCCCCAGGUAUGAGGAGGGGGUGGUCUUAGGGUUCUGUUCCAGGUCUGCCCCGCCCCCCUCCCAGCCAUGCCCCAGGCAGAACUUGGAAUUCAGGUGUGCACCUGCAGGCUGAGGGGCUCUGUGAGCAGGUGCUGCUCACACAGGGAGUUCAGGCGCCAGCCAAGCCCCUGUGCUGCUGGGAUAGGCCUGCUUCACUUAGGGAGCACUGCCUCAAGACAGGUAAAGCCCCCUCGUUUGCCCCCACCCCCAUGGGGCCGCUCAGGAGAGAAACUCCCAUUCACCCCUUUCCCAGGGUGCUCUCUCUCUAGGUGGCAUGCCAGCCCCCAAACACAAGUGGCUUUUGGGCCCAGGUGGGUCAGCCUGCUGCCCCUGCCCCAUACCCCCUCGGGCCAUUGGGACCCCUGCCCUUCAGAUGUCCUAGGGUCUAGGAGUGGGGCCAGUCACUGUGGGAAGAGGCCAGGGGCUUGGCCGGAGAGGCAGCCCAGGGCAGGACCCAGUCCUGAGUCCUGGAGCAGGGCCAGGGAGGCGCCCAUCCCGCCCCAGCCAGCCGCCCUCUCUGCUGUUUCUUCUAUUUGUUCUUCUUUUCACCCACAGCUCUGUGUUCCUGUCAUCCCUCCUUUCAGCAAAAGUCCUGUUCCCGUUCCCUCUGUCCCCACCCACUCCUGUUCCCCCAAGAAAAUAAGCUAUCGUUGUAUUUGCAAUCUAUGGAUUAGAGGUUUAAGUAUUUAUUAUUAUUGGUUAAUUAUUAUUAAUUAUGUAAAUUUGCCUCCCAUAUGUCUGUUGCGUUGGGUUUCUGAGGAGACCCUGGGUGAGGAGGAUGCACUGGCUUCCCGCUUCUCGCCCCCCACCCCUGUGCUGUCCGGGAGACAGUGGUCUGGGGCCACUGGUUGGGCCCCCUUCUCCCUUCCCCCUUCCCCUUGUCCCUUCUGCAGGCCGUUGAGGGGGGCUGUCUGUCUCAGUCUGUCUCUGCUCCCACUCUUGAGGCACUGGUUACCGCAAAGUGAGCAGCCAGCAGGGGGGCGAAGGUCCUGUGUUGGCCACUGCCUCCUCCAGUGCUGCAGGAGGCGGGCUGAGGCCCCACCUGGUGGCUUUCACCUGACCCAGCCCUGAGUCCUCUCCAAGCCUCUCUCCGGCCCCUCCCACCUGGCCACUGCCUCCUCCAGUGCUGCGGGAGGCGGGCCAGGGCCCCACCUGGUGGCUUUCACCUGACCCAGCCCUGAGUCCUCUCCAAGCCUCUCUCCGGCCCCUCCCACCUGGCCACUGCCUGGCAUUGGGAUCGCCCCAAAAUGGACCCGGCCCCUCCUGUUAUUUGCUGGGAAGUCCAGCGGAGGAGAGGGUGCAGGUCCCCCGCUGAGCCUCCAGUCUCUGUAGACUGGGCUGCCGGCCCUUCAGCCCCCCUUGGAGCCCCUCCCGCCACAGCCGCACCUUCUGCUCCCGGCCCCUCCCUUUGUAUUUGGAGACAAUGUGUUGUAAUAAAGCUUAAAGUGGAUGUUUUC